AUCUAUCAUCCCACUACCACCAUGCUGGCCUCAGGGAUGCUUCUGGUGGCCUUGCUGGUCUGCCUGACUGUAAUGGUCUUGAUGUCUGUUUGGCAGCAGAGGAAGAGCAAGGGGAAGCUGCCUCCGGGACCCACCCCAUUGCCCUUCAUUGGAAACUACCUGCAGCUGAACACAGAGCAGAUGUACAACUCCCUCAUGAAGAUCAGUGAGCGCUAUGGCCCCGUGUUCACCAUUCACUUGGGGCCCCGGCGGGUCGUGGUGCUGUGUGGACAUGAUGCCGUCAGGGAGGCUCUGGUGGACCAGGCUGAGGAGUUCAGCGGGCGAGGCGAGCAAGCCACCUUCGACUGGGUCUUCAAAGGCUAUGGCGUGGUAUUCAGCAACGGGGAGCGCGCCAAGCAGCUCCGGCGCUUCUCCAUCGCCACCCUGCGGGACUUCGGGGUGGGCAAGCGAGGCAUCGAGGAGCGCAUCCAGGAGGAGGCGGGCUUCCUCAUCGACGCCCUCCGGGGCACUGGCGGCGCCAAUAUCGAUCCCACCUUCUUCCUGAGCCGCACAGUCUCCAAUGUCAUCAGCUCCAUUGUCUUUGGGGACCGCUUUGACUAUAAGGACAAAGAGUUCCUGUCACUGUUGCGCAUGAUGCUAGGAAUCUUCCAGUUCACGUCAACCUCCACGGGGCAGCUCUAUGAGAUGUUCUCUUCGGUGAUGAAACACCUGCCAGGACCACAGCAACAGGCCUUUCAGUUGCUGCAAGGGCUGGAGGACUUCAUAGCCAAGAAGGUGGAGCACAACCAGCGCACGCUGGAUCCCAAUUCCCCACGGGACUUCAUUGACUCCUUUCUCAUCCGCAUGCAGGAGGAGGAGAAGAACCCCAACACGGAGUUCUACUUGAAAAACCUGGUGAUGACCACGUUGAACCUCUUCAUUGGGGGCACCGAGACCGUCAGCACCACCCUGCGCUAUGGCUUCUUGCUGCUCAUGAAGCACCCAGAGGUGGAGGCCAAGGUCCAUGAGGAGAUUGACAGAGUGAUCGGCAAGAACCGGCAGCCCAAGUUUGAGGACCGGGCCAAGAUGCCCUACAUGGAGGCAGUGAUCCACGAGAUCCAAAGAUUUGGAGACGUGAUCCCCAUGAGUUUGGCCCGCAGAGUCAAAAAGGACACCAAGUUUCGGGAUUUCUUCCUCCCUAAGGGCACCGAAGUGUACCCUAUGCUGGGCUCUGUGCUGAGAGACCCCAGUUUCUUCUCCAACCCCCAGGACUUCAAUCCCCAGCACUUCCUGAAUGAGAAGGGGCAGUUUAAGAAGAGUGAUGCUUUUGUGCCCUUUUCCAUCGGAAAGCGGAACUGUUUCGGAGAAGGCCUGGCCAGAAUGGAGCUCUUUCUCUUCUUCACCACCGUCAUGCAGAACUUCCGCCUCAAGUCCUCCCAGUCACCUAAGGACAUUGACGUGUCCCCCAAACACGUGGGCUUUGCCACGAUCCCACGAAACUACACCAUGAGCUUCCUGCCCCGCUGAGCGAGGGCUGUGCCGGUGCAGGUCUGGUGGGCGGGGCCAGGGAAAGGGCAGGGCCAAGACCGGGCUUGGGAGAGGGGCGCAGCUAAGACUGGGGGCAGGAUGGCGGAAAGGAAGGGGCGUGGUGGCUAGAGGGAAGAGAAGAAACAGAAGCGGCUCAGUUCACCUUGAUAAGGUGCUUCCGAGCUGGGAUGAGAGGAAGGAAACCCUUACAUUAUGCUAUGAAGAGUAGUAAUAAUAGCAGCUCUUAUUUCCUGA